GAAGACGGAGGGCGGAGCCGGCUUCGGGACUGCGGAGACUACACACCGAGCGAGCGCCUGGGCCCGAAGGGAGCGAUGCUGUGGUUCCAGGGCGCCAUUCCGGCCGCCAUCGCGACGGCCAAAAGGAGCGGCGCGGUCUUCGUGGUGUUCGUGGCAGGUGAUGAUGAACAGUCUACACAGAUGGCUGCAAGUUGGGAAGAUGAUAAAGUUACAGAAGCAUCUUCAAACAGUUUUGUUGCUAUUAAAAUCGAUACCAAAAGUGAAGCCUGCCUACAGUUUUCACAAAUCUAUCCUGUAGUGUGUGUUCCAUCCAGUUUCUUUAUUGGAGACAGUGGAAUUCCCUUGGAAGUAAUAGCAGGAAGUGUUUCUGCAGAUGAACUUGUUACAAGAAUUCACAAGGUCCGACAGAUGCAUUUGCUAAAAAGUGAAACAUCAGUAGCAAAUGGCAGUCAGUCAGAAAGUUCAGUGUCUACUCCAUCUGCGUCAUUUGAACCUAACAACACUUGUGAAAACUCUCAGUCCAGAAAUGCAGAGCUUUGUGAGAUACCACCCACUUCUGAUACAAAGUCAGAUACUGCAACAGGAGGAGAAAGUGCAGGCCAUGCCACUUCCUCUCAGGAGCCUAGUGGAUGCUCAGAUCAGAGACCUGCAGAGGACCUCAACAUCCGAGUGGAAAGACUAACAAAAAAACUUGAAGAAAGGAGAGAAGAGAAAAGAAAAGAGGAAGAACAGAGAGAAAUUAAGAAGGAAAUUGAGAGGAGAAAAACUGGAAAAGAAAUGUUGGAUUAUAAAAGAAAACAAGAAGAAGAAUUAACAAAAAGAAUGCUGGAGGAAAGAAACAGAGAGAAAGCAGAAGAUAGGGCAGCUCGAGAACGUAUAAAACAGCAGAUUGCAUUGGACCGUGCAGAGAGAGCUGCUCGUUUUGCAAAGACAAAGGAAGAAGUAGAGGCUGCCAAAGCUGCUGCCUUGCUAGCAAAACAGGCAGAAAUGGAAGUCAAGAGGGAAUCUUAUGCAAGAGAAAGAAGCACUGUUGCAAGAAUUCAAUUCCGUCUUCCUGAUGGUUCUUCCUUUACAAAUCAGUUCCCUUCUGAUGCUCCUCUAGAAGAGGCAAGGCAGUUUGCUGCACAGACUGUUGGCAACACUUACGGUAAUUUUUCGUUAGCAACCAUGUUUCCCAGGAGGGAAUUUACCAAAGAAGAUUAUAAAAAGAAGUUACUGGAUUUGGAACUUGCCCCAAGCGCUUCGGUGGUACUGUUGCCAGCAGGAAGACCAACUGCAUCCAUUGUACACUCUUCCAGCGGAGACAUUUGGACCUUGUUGGGAACAGUGCUUUAUCCAUUCCUUGCCAUCUGGAGAUUAAUUAGCAAUUUCUUGUUUAGUAAUCCGCCUCCCACACAGACUUCAGUGAGAGUAACAUCGUCAGAACCCCCAAACCCUGCAUCAUCUAGCAAAUCAGAAAAAAGGGAACCAGUGAGAAAAAGAGUGCUGGAAAAACGUGGAGACGACUUUAAAAAGGAGGGGAAAAUUUAUAGAUUAAGGACUCAAGAUGAUGGUGAAGAUGAAAACAACACUUGGAAUGGAAAUUCCACUCAACAGAUGUAGUGUGACAAGUAUAAUAUGUGCAAUAAUCAUUGUUUCUCUUAUGAUUUAAUUCAACUAAAAUUCUACUGGAGAAGUGGGACUGCUUUAUAUUUUCCAACUGGUCUAUAAAAUGUCUCUUUAUUCCUGCUUAGUGGGUGUGGGUUGAAGGUGUUUAACUCAGAAAAGUAAAGACAGGAAAUAACUCUCUGCUAGGUCCUUGCUUAUAUGGCAACCACUGCUAGAACCCUAAAAGAACCAAAAAUCUGCCACAGCCUGCCUCCAUCAGCUUCUUAUUUAGUAUUUCAUAUGCCCAUUAGCCCUAUGCUUCAGAUGACACGUUUUGUUUAGAGCUACUUUGCUCCAAGACUCUUAAGCCCAAAGUAACUGGUAUGUCACUGAGUAACUUGACUCGGUGUCAGAGCAUUUUAACUAGCCACUCAGAUGAGAAUUUAUGUUUAACUUCUCUUUUUACUCAUCAGCUGCAAGCAAAAUCUUGUAGUUUUUAAUCUUAAACACUGAAUAAAAAAACUUUCCCCUAAAUUGGAAUGAUCUUAGUUUUGCUUUGAGUUUUGUUAUCUAGCAUCUUUUUGUUGCACAGGGCUCUAUUGAGGUCCUAUGUCUCUGAUUUUUUUUUUUCCCCAGUAUUGCCCUGGAGCUGUCUCUGGAAAGUAGCUGGCGAGGUUACCUUAACUAUCACUGAAGAAAGAAAUUUUCUGACACACUGAUGGCAUGUGACUUGUCUCCUAAGUCAGUGAGGCAUCACUUUGUUUGCAUAAAGUAUACGGUUUGUUAAGGCCUUUGUUCUUGUGAGAUGCAAAACAGCUGCUAGUCUGCAACCUAGUUUUCCCUCUCACCUUUAACUGACGUUUUGUCCUCAAUAAUUACACAAGGACCUAGAGUACCUAUAGGACAAAAAGUAUAGAAUAAAAAUAUGCCUUUAGUCAUUUGGUUUUUCUUAAAAAGUUGAGAUUCUUAAUCUGACUUACAUGUUACUUUAUCCGUAUGUCUUUGUUAGUGGAGACCGCUAAACUAAUGAUGUUUGAAAACAGUUCCUCUGUUUUAGAUUGGAAGAUAGCACUCUAGAGUGGACAUACGGAAAGACUGUGACUUUAUUUUGUAAUGGGAGGAAGAAAUUUUCUCAGAGCAAACUUUCUAUUUUUUACCUGUGAAAUAACAGUGACUUUUUAAAAUGGUGACAGUGUUGGCAAGGAAACAGCAACACAGGCUGCGCUGUUGGUAGGAGUGAAAACCAGUAUAAUUCUUCUGAAAAACAUUUAUCAGAAACUUAAAAUAUUUCAUACCGUUUGAUCCAGUAGCUUCUUCUAAAUCAUAAAUGCAGACAAUGUUUAGGUAAAGACAUACUCAUUAAGUGUUAUUUAUUUUACUCAAGAACUGGAAACCAACUAAAUGCCUUCUAUAGAAGUAAUUUUUGAUGAGGAGAAAUGGUACAAUACUAAUUAACAACUUGGUUUAACAUGUUUACUGAGCAUCUGUUAAGUGUUGGGGGAAAAAGCAGCAGGAUCCAGAGCUAUAGGUACAGUGUGAUCUCAGCUUUGCAAACACAUUUUCUACAUAGAUAGUACUAGGUAUUAAUAGAUAUGUAAAGAAAGAAAUCACACCAUUAAUAAUGGUAAGAUUGGUUUAUGUGAUUUUAGUGGUAUUUUUGGCACCCUUAUAUAUGUUUUCCAAACUUUCAGCAGUGAUAUUAUUUCCAUAACUUAAAAAGUGAGUUUGAAAAAGAAAAUCUCCAGCAAGCAUCUCAUUUAAAUAAAGGUUUGUCAUCUUUAAAAAUACAGCAAUAUGUGACUUUUUAAAAAAGCUGUCAAAUAGGUGUGACCCUACUAAUAAUUAUUAGAAAUACAUUUAAAAACAUCGAGUACCUCAAGUCAGUUUGCCUUGAAAAAUAUCAAAUAUAACUCUUAGAGAAAUGUACAUAAAAGAAUGCUUCGUAAUUUUGGAGUAGGAGGUUCCCUCCUCAAUUUUGUAUUUUUAAAAGUACAUGGUAAAAAAAAAAAUUCACAACAGUAUAUAAGGCUGUAAAAUGAGAAUUCUGCCCCCUCACCUCUUACCCCAGUACUAUUCUCCAGAGGUAAUCUAUUAACAAUUUCUUAUGUAAUUUUCAGAAAAUUUGUAUGCGUAUAUAAGCAAAUAUGUAAUCUUUAUUUUUUAAAUAAAUGGGAUCAUAUUAUA